CACUGGCGGAGAAAAUCCCCUUCUUUUUUUUCUCUCUCUUUUUUUCUUUUUGAGACGGAAUCUCACUCUUUCACCCAGACUGGAGGGCAGCGGCGAGAUCUCGGCUCACUGCAACCUCCACCUCCCAGGUUCAAGCAAUUCUCCUGCCUCAGCCUUCCGAGUAGCUGGGAUUACAGGUGCCCGCCACCACGCCCAGCUAAUUUUUGUAUUUUUAGUAGAGACAGGAUUUUACCAUGUUGGCCAUGCUGGUCUCAAACUCCUGACCUCGUGUGAUCCCCCUGCUUCAGCCUCUCAAACUGCUGGGAUUAUAGGCAUGAGCCACUGCGCCUGGCCAACAAUCCCCUUCUAAAGGCAGGUGGUGUCUCCAGCACCAGGGCCAUACGGCUGCAACACCCCUACAAGUGCCGGGUCUGCCAGACAACCACGACCAACUAGUCCCAGAUAACCUUGAGGCCUGGGCACUGGCUGGGCCCCGAGGGCUCUUCCCAAAGCGUACCCUGGUCAUCUGGAAGAGGAUCGGAGCUGGCCUGGUGGUGACAGUGGCCUUGCUUCCUAGGAUGGAUGGCAGAUGGCAAUGUUCCUGCUGGGCCUGGUUCCUGCUGGUUCUGGCAGUUGUAGCUGGGGACACAGUGUCAACCGGGUCCACGGACAACAGCCCAACAUCCAAUAGCCUGGAGGGGGGCACCGACGCCACGGCCUUCUGGUGGGGGGAGUGGACCAAGUGGACGGCGUGUUCCCGCAGUUGCGGGGGUGGGGUGACAUCCCAGGAGCGGCACUGCCUGCAGCAGAGGAGGAAGUCCGUCCCGGGCCCCGGGAACAGGACCUGCACGGGCACGUCCAAGCGGUACCAGCUCUGCAGAGUGCAGGAGUGUCCGCCGGACGGGAGGAGCUUCCGCGAGGAGCAGUGCGUCUCCUUCAACUCCCACGUGUACAACGGGCGGACGCACCAGUGGAAGCCUCUGUACCCGGAUGACUAUGUCCACAUCUCCAGCAAACCGUGUGACCUGCACUGUACCACCGUGGACGGCCAGCGGCAGCUCAUGGUCCCCGCCCGCGACGGCACAUCCUGCAAGCUCACUGACCUGCGAGGGGUUUGCGUGUCUGGAAAAUGUGAGCCCAUCGGCUGUGACGGGGUGCUUUUCUCCACCCACACACUGGACAAGUGUGGCAUCUGCCAGGGGGACGGUAGCAGCUGCACCCACGUGACGGGCAACUAUCGCAAGGGGAAUGCCCACCUUGGUUACUCUCUGGUGACCCACAUCCCGGCUGGUGCCCGAGACAUCCAGAUUGUAGAGAGGAAGAAGUCCGCUGACGUGCUAGCUCUUGCAGACGAAGCUGGCUACUACUUCUUCAACGGCAACUACAAGGUGGACAGCCCCAAGAACUUCAACAUCGCAGGCACGGUGGUCAAGUACAGGCGGCCCAUGGAUGUCUAUGAGACCGGAAUCGAGUACAUCGUGGCACAGGGGCCCACCAACCAGGGCCUGAAUGUCAUGGUGUGGAACCAGAACGGCAAAAGCCCCUCCAUCACCUUCGAGUACACGCUGCUGCAGCCGCCACACGAGAGCCGCCCCCAGCCCAUCUACUAUGGCUUCUCCGAGAGCGCUGAGAGCCAGGGCCUGGACGGGGCCGGGCUGAUGGGCUUCGUCCCGCACAACGGCUCCCUCUACGGCCAGGCCUCCUCAGAGCGGCUGGGCCUGGACAACCGGCUGUUCGGCCACCCGGGCCUGGACAUGGAGCUGGGCCCCAGCCAGGGCCAGGAGACCAACGAGGUGUGCGAGCAGGCCGGCGGCGGGGCCUGCGAGGGGCCCCCCAGGGGCAAGGGCUUCCGAGACCGCAACGUCACGGGGACUCCUCUCACCGGGGACAAGGAUGACGAAGAGGUUGACACCCACUUCGCCUCCCAGGAGUUCUUCUCGGCUAACGCCAUCUCUGACCAGCUGCUGGGCGCAGGCUCUGACUUGAAGGACUUCACCCUCAAUGAGACUGUGAACAGCAUCUUUGCACAGGGCGCCCCAAGGAGCUCCCUGGCCGAGAGCUUCUUCGUGGAUUAUGAGGAGAACGAGGGGGCUGGCCCUUACCUGCUCAACGGGUCCUACCUGGAGCUGAGCAGCGACAGGGUUGCCAACAGCUCCUCCGAGGCCCCAUUCCCCAACGUUAGCACCAGCCUGCUCACCUCGGCCGGGAACAGGACUCACAAGGCCAGGACCAGGCCCAAGGCGCGCAAGCAAGGCGUGAGUCCCGCGGACAUGUACCGGUGGAAGCUCUCGUCCCACGAGCCCUGCAGUGCCACCUGCACCACAGGGGUCAUGUCUGCGUACGCCAUGUGUGUCCGCUAUGAUGGCGUCGAGGUGGAUGACAGCUACUGUGACGCCCUGACCCGUCCCGAGCCUGUCCACGAGUUCUGCGCUGGGAGGGAGUGCCAGCCCAGGUGGGAGACGAGCAGCUGGAGCGAGUGUUCGCGCACCUGCGGAGAGGGCUACCAGUUCCGCGUCGUGCGCUGCUGGAAGAUGCUCUCGCCCGGCUUCGACAGCUCCGUGUACAGCGACCUGUGCGAGGCAGCCGAGGCCGUGCGGCCCGAGGAACGCAAGACCUGCCGGAACCCCGCCUGCGGGCCCCAGUGGGAGAUGUCGGAGUGGUCCGAGUGCACUGCCAAGUGUGGGGAGCGCAGUGUGGUGACCAGGGACAUCCGCUGCUCGGAGGAUGAGAAGCUGUGUGACCCCAACACCAGGCCUGUAGGGGAGAAGAACUGCACGGGCCCGCCCUGUGACCGGCAGUGGACCGUCUCCGACUGGGGACCGUGCAGUGGAAGCUGCGGGCAAGGCCGCACCAUCAGGCACGUGUACUGCAAGACCAGCGACGGACGGGUAGUACCUGAGUCCCAGUGCCAGAUGGAGACCAAGCCUCUGGCCAUCCACCCCUGUGGGGACAAAAACUGUCCCGCCCACUGGCUGGCCCAGGACUGGGAGCGGUGCAACACCACCUGCGGGCGCGGGGUCAAGAAGCGGCUGGUGCUCUGCAUGGAGCUGGCCAACGGGAAGCCGCAGACGCGCAGUGGCCCCGAGUGCGGGCUCGCCAAGAAGCCUCCCGAGGAGAGCACGUGUUUCGAGAGGCCCUGCUUCAAGUGGUACACCAGCCCCUGGUCAGAGUGCACCAAGACCUGCGGGGUGGGCGUGAGGAUGCGAGACGUCAAGUGCUACCAGGGGACCGACAUCGUCCGUGGUUGCGAUCCGUUGGUGAAGCCCGUUGGCAGACAGGCCUGUGAUCUGCAGCCCUGCCCCACGGAGCCCCCAGAUGACAGCUGCCAGGACCAGCCAGGCACCAACUGUGCCCUGGCCAUCAAAGUGAACCUCUGCGGGCACUGGUACUACAGCAAGGCGUGCUGCCGCUCCUGCAGGCCCCCCCACUCCUAGGCCCGGCAGCUGCAGCCCCUUCCAGAUGAAGACCAAGCGCCCCUCCUGGGGCUGCUGCAGCUUCUGGGGCCUCCACAGACCCCCCUCCUGCGGGGCACGCUGGCCUAAGAGACGUGGCACUGAGCCUCGGCUGUCGAGAGGGGACUUCCCACGGCCCGUGGACCUUUGUGCUCCUGGGGCAGAGCCUCCGGCACCCAGUGGCCUCCCCCAGACAGAGCCACCCCUGCCGUGGGAACCUGUCCGUGUUCCUGCGUGGAUCCUGUGUUUGUGGCUCCCACUCCCCAGCCCCCCAGCAGCCCCCAGCCGAGGGGCCCAGGGCCCACAGCCAGCGGUGGAGGUGUCUUGCUCCGGGCCCGUAGCCCACGCCCUCUCUGGGUGGCAGGGCCUUCUGAAGGAAACUUGCAGGCGAGCCCAACGUGGUGGGGGGCCUUCCUCCCUCAGAGGCCAUGGGGUGAGAGGGGCUCAGGCAGCCAAGGAGGCCCAGGCGUGCUCCCUCUUAUGGAGCCCCUCCCAUGGAGCUCUCUUCCCGCCGCACUUUCUACCCCGGGCAGAGGCGCUUGCCCACGGGACGUUUGGGGAUGGACCUCGGCCCCCGCCCCUGCAGUCAGCGUCAGUGCUCAUCUACGUUAAUAAAGUGGUCCUAUUUAUGGCGGCA